AAGCGCACAGCGAAAACAAAGAUGGCGGCCGUGCCGGGGUCGGUGGCCGCGGCGGCUGUGGGGCUACGCGCGGGCCGGGCCCACUGAGGCGGCGGCGCAGGGAGCGGGGCUGCGGGUUCGCGGCGGCGGCGGCAGGAGAGCGGCGGGAGCGCGCGGCGCCCCUAACUUCUAGUCGGGGGAGCGCGCCGGCAUCCGCCCGCCGGGCCGGCCGGCCGCUAUGUCCGGCGCCGAGGAGGCCGGCGGGGGCGGCCCGGCCGCGGGGCCCGCGGGCUCCGUGCCGGCCGGGGUCGGGGUCGGGGUCGGAGCCGGGCCCGGGGCGGCCGCCGGGCAGGCGGCGGCGGCGGCUCUGGGCGAGGCGGCGGGGCCUGGGCUCCCGGACGAGGCGGGCUUGGCGGGCGCCCGGCAGCUACAGCUGCAGGAGGCGGCCGGCGACCCCGACGCGCCGCCCAAGAAGCGGCUGCGGGCAGCCGAGGCGGCCGAGGCGGCGGCGGCGGCGGCGGCGGCCGGCAGCGGGAAACUGGAGGAGCGGCUCUACUCGGUGCUGUGCUGCACCGUGUGCCUGGACCUGCCCAAGGCCUCCGUGUACCAGUGUACUAAUGGUCACUUGAUGUGCGCUGGCUGUUUUAUCCACCUACUAGCAGAUGCCCGGCUGAAGGAGGAGCAGGCCACGUGCCCCAAUUGUCGUUGUGAGAUCAGUAAGAGCCUCUGCUGCCGGAACCUGGCCGUGGAGAAAGCCGUGAGCGAGCUGCCUUCAGAGUGUGGCUUCUGCCUGCGCCAGUUUCCCCGCUCCCUCCUGGAGAGGCACCAGAAAGAGGAAUGCCAGGACAGGGUAACCCAGUGCAAGUACAAACGCAUCGGCUGCCCAUGGCACGGCCCCUUCCAUGAGCUGACGGUGCACGAGGCUGCGUGCGCCCACCCGACCAAGACAGGCAGUGAGCUGAUGGAGAUCCUGGAUGGGAUGGACCAGAGCCACCGCAAGGAGAUGCAGCUGUACAACAGCAUCUUCAGCCUGCUCAGCUUCGAGAAGAUUGGCUACACAGGUGAGGCGCCCCGCCGCCUGCUGCAUGCCACACAGGUGUGGGUUGGGGGGCUGGCAGCCAGGAGUCUGGGGGCAGCAGGCUCUGGGCACUGGGCACUGACAGCGCCGGACAGCCGGGCUCUGGACAAGCUCCCGGUGGACAGGUGGACACCUCGGUCGAGAAGACAGGCCGGAGACUGAGUGGAAGGAGGGGCCGAGGCAGACCCCAGGUGCACACCUGUGUGGCUCUCACAGCAGCCCCGCCCACCUGUCCUCGCCACCCUGGCUUCACCAUCCCUGCAAGGUGGCAUCUCACUGUGGGGCUCCAGAGCCUCAAGACAGUCAGGGUCUAACCAGAAAGUGGGCAGGUCUCAGGGGGCCUGGGAGCUAGGGGCCUGCCCCUCGGACCCUGGGGCAAGAAGAGCACCCUGCCGAGUGAGGUCCUACCUGCAGGCAGUCACUGCCCCGGCCAUGGGCCUCUCAAGGCUGGCACGAAGCCAUUCAGGGAGAGGGCUCCACAACAAGCUGAGGGUGCCCGACUCAAACUGUAGAACCGGGAGUGGACACCCACAGACGCCCAGGCUGGAUGCGUGCGCAGGCACACUGGAUCUCGUGGCUCUCUGGGCCGCUGCCACCGCCUUUGAACGUGUCGGGGAGCAGGAGCCAGGCCAGAGCCUGGCCCAGAGGACAGCGAGAAGCACCUGUUGAUGCUGGGGCCACUGGAGGAAGCUCCAUCCCUCUACUCUCAGCCCACACCAGGCGGCCAGCUCAGAGCACCAGGCGUGGCGCAAGCAGGGUGGUCGUGGGCAGCCAGUCCCGCCCUGCUGCCUGGACUGUGCCCAGCGGGAUGUGGGCCCGAGCAGGCCAGAGAGGCCGAGGGCCUGGGGUCUCUGCGGCAGCCACAGCCCGUGGUGAGUAGCAGCCUUAGCUGUCCUGGAGAUACCGGGGCCUCGUGGAGUCUAGGCAGGCUGGGGCACUGUGGCUGUGGCCGUGGCCAGGUGAGAAGCCCCAUUCGCGCAGGAAAGACUGGCCACCUGGGAACCCACGCCUCCACGGAGGGACUUGCCGGCCACAGGCUGUGGGCUGCCCAAGAGGACUGUGCAGGCAGGGCUGCCUGCUGAUUGGCAGCUCCGGAUCAGGCCCGGUGCCUGCAGACCUGGUGCUCCCCUCGGGCAGGGCUGGGUGCCGCAGCCGCCUGCUGGCUUUUCUGGCAGCUCCUCUGUAUCAGAACCAAUAAAGUGCACUUGUUCUCGGAA